GACGGGAGCUAGAGCCCAUGUCUUGUGGCGUCAGAUGCGGCUCUUUCCCUGCUCUACUCUGCCCCCUGUCGUAGGAGGAAUGGACGAAGAAAGUGGAGCUGUUCAGCCUGGAGAAGAGAAGACUCAGGGGGACAGGACUGCUGGCUUCGUGGCUCUGAAGGGCUGUCCCAGGCAGAGGGAGCAGCUGUGUUCUGAGUGACCGCAAGAGUCAAACAACAAGCAGGGGCUUUGGGUUCGAAUCCUAACUCUGCCAGUUUGAAUCCAGACUCUGCUAUAUCUUAGCUGUGUGGCCUUGGGCAGUCACAUGAUCUCUCUGGGCCUCAGUUUUCUCUUCUGUAGAGUGGGGAAGAGGGUUUUUAGAGGAUUAAAUGACAUGACAUCGGUGCAGCCCCUGACAUACACGAGGCACUAAAAAUAUCAGUCUUCUCAUUCCACCAUAUCAGGUUGGUGAGAAAUGCAGAGAGGCAGCUUUCAGCUCCAAGAGAAGAAGAACUUUGUCACACUUAGAGGCUUCUGCCAGUGGAAGGGAGGGAGCAAGCUCCACUUACGAGAAGCGUGCAAGCAGGGGCUGGUGGGGAUUCCGUCUGCAGCUGGGGAGUUAGAUUCAGUAACCCUUAAAAUUUUUUGAGCCUUAAGAUUCCAUCAGUCCCAGCUGGGCCUGGUGGCUCACACCUGUAAUCCCAGCACUUUGGGAGGCCAAGGUGGGCGAUCGCUUGAGCCCAGGAGUUUGAGACCAGCCUGGCCAACAUGGUGAAACCCCAUCUUUACUAAAAAUACAAAAAUUAGCCAGGCAUAGUGGUGGGCGCCUGUAAUCCCAGCUACUCAGGAGGCUGAGGAAGGAGAAUCACUUGAGCCCAGGAGGUUGCAGUGAGCUAAGAUCGUGCCACUGCACUCCAGCCUGGGUGACAGAGUGAGACUCCGUCUCAAAAAAAAAAAAAUAAUAAUAAUAAUAAUAAUAAAAAAAAGAUUCCAUCAGUCCCUGGGCAGGUUUUGGCCACAUGUUUACUCUGGGCCUCUCUCUCUCCGCUGCCCCCAACUAAGUGCCGGGACAUGGAGCAUAAUAGGCCCCAGCCUCUGUCCUUAGGAGGCUUAGUGACCUGGGUGCAGUGGAGCUUAUUGGGAGCUGAGCUGGUCAGGGAAGGCUUCGUGAAGGAUGGGCCUCAAUGAUGUAAAGAGCCAAUGAACAGAUAGUGUCACUAAAAAUUAAAAUAAGUAAGUAAAUAAAUAAAGAGGCAAAAAGGGUACACUGCAGCCAGGAUGACAGUGAGAGCCUCAAACGCUGGCUCCAGAGCUCACGCCCAUAUGCCCUGUGCUCUGUGAUUGGUGUGUAGCAGGCACUAUGUAUAAUGUAUCUCAUUUAAUCCUCUUAAGAAACCUAAGGGGCACGUAUUAAUGCCCCCAUUUUGCAGGUAAGAAAACUGAGUCUGAGAGGUCAAAUGACUUACUCAAAGUCACACAGUUUAAGCAGUAAAGCAAAGAUUCAAAUCCAGCUCUGACUGUCCCCAGUGCCACCUCCACAGAGGUGACCUCGUGCUUUUAGGGAGGAUGGCCAAGGUGUGCCAGGAUGGCACAGUGGGGGCAUAGCUCAUGGCCAAUCUCAUUGUCACCAGGCCCAGCAGAAAAGGAAAAACAACUUCACAAUGCCAGGCCCUGCCAUCCUGUCACUAGCAAACCGCACCCCAUCUCCUCACCCUGUGGGUUGCCUAAAUGCCCCAUCAGCCUCCCUGUUCCCUCCCUGUCCCAGACCGUGGGAGUUAAAACAAACACUACCCAGGGUUGAUUGUCAGUGGGAACCACUCACUGUUUCCCCAGUCCAAGGAACGGAAACAAAGUGAGCAGGCAGAUGCUAGGUGAGGCCACACCACGAGGGGCCAGCCCCAGACACAGGAAUCUAACCAGAUAGUUGGCUUAGGGUUAAGGGCCUUUUAGAUUCUAAAGUUUCACAGUAGAAAGGAUGUCGGGGUCUCAAUUCCAAGCCCUGUCUAGGAAGGAAGCCCCCCUGCAGCCUCCUGAUGGCUUGAUGGUAUCUGGCACCUGACUGUACAUACCCCCACUCCUACUCCAGAUAGGUGACACACUUCCAACACUGUGAAUUGCUCAGCCCAAAGGGCAUCUGACUUCACACUGAGCUGAGCCUAUCCUGUGUCCCUGGACUUGCCCAUUGGUGCCAGCUCUGCUUUGAGGAUCCACAGAGCCUACCUGCCCUCAGACCUGCCACAGCCCUUCAAAGGGCAAGAGGCACAACCAUGACCCUCAGGCUAGCUCUUGAUUCCAGGCCAGAGACCCAGUCCUUUCAAUUAUGCUUUAAUGCUUUACAGACCACAGUGUGGGAACCCGCCCUCAUCCCUGCCACCUUCUCUCCAAUUUUUCUGUAACUCGGGAGCAUGCAGUGGCAGGCCUGUGCCGAAGGACCCAUCCCCAUCUCAUCUCAUGCUUGUUGCCUGCCGCUAUGAUAUAAUCCCUGGGCCUUUGGAGUUUCUUCCAUAUCCUGGUCCUUGGCAUCUGGGCUGGGGGGGUCCAUGGACAGUGCUGGACAUUUCCUGAUUCCUGGAACUCAGUCCCAGGAUUAGGGUUUUCUGUUCCCCUUGGCGGUAAUCCCACGCUGAUUCCCAUAAGCAGGGCCAGUUCUUGGUCUUCUUAAAGGCAGUGCUGGCCUAGCAGAGGCCUUGCUGGUUGCAUCUGUUCUUUCUGGCCAGAGACCUUGGUGGGUAACAGCUGGUGCAGCCUCACAGCCCAUGUGCUCAGGGCCUCAGAGCCAUGUGUGGUGCCAGUGGCCAGCACCCCAUGAGAUGCAAACAUCAGGGGAUCCAGCUAAUACCUCAUUCCCCCUUGGGGCCUGGCCUAGACUGGGUAUGUGGGGUGUGUGUGUGUGUGUGUGUGUGUGUGUGUGUGUGUGUGUGUGUGUAUUUGUUAUCUAUCUAUCCAUCCAUCCAUCCAUCCAUCCAUCCAGGGAUUCAUUCAUUCUACAUGCCAAAUGUGGGCCAGGCUCAAGGGACCCAGAGAGGAGAGCCCUCUGGGAGUCCCCAGUCUGGUAGAGGAAGCAGGAGUAGACACAAUGAGAGCACAUUAGAAACAGGCACAAUCACAGAUGGAAGCCAGGUGCUGUGGGUGCCCCAAGGAGGAAUUGCCUCGGGUGGAUUAGGGAAGACUUCCCAGCUAAGGCUUGGAGCACAGGUAGGAGUUCAUUUGGUGCUAAUAGUAGAAGUCGUGGCCAGGUGCAGUGGCUCACGCCUGUAAUCCCAGCUUGUGCUUUGGGAGGCCAAGGCAGGUGGAUCA